GCGGGCGCAGGCUGCGGGGUCGGCACGGAAGAUGCACGCGAGGCUCCUGGGGCUCUCGGCCCUGCUGCAGGCGGCCGAGCAGAGCGCGCGCCUUUACACCGUGGCUUACUACUUCACCACAGGACGGCUUCUGUGGGGGUGGCUGGCCCUUGCUGUCCUCCUGCCCGGGUUCUUGGUCCAGGCCCUGAGCUACCUGUGGUUCCGAGCAGACGGGCAUCCAGGGCAUUGCUCCUUGAUGAUGCUGCACCUCCUACAGCUUGGUGUUUGGAAGCGCCCACAAAUCCACUUGUAAAUGCAGCAUGAGAUGACAGAAGAAGGCCUAUCUCAUCCUUAGCAUGCACCUUGGUUUAGCAAUUUUUCUUUAGUGAAAGUUCAAGGUUGUCAAAAGGAAAGUUAAGGUAAACUCUAAAGGCACUGGGACGCUGCACUGACCAGUCUGCAGAAGGAACUGGAGGCUCCCCACCGAGGCUGGCUGCAGCUGCAGGAGGCCGACCUGUCGGCCCUUCGACUCUUGGAGGCCCUGCUGCAGACUGGGCCCCACCUGCUGCUUCAGACAUAUGUUUUUCUAGCCUCAGACUUCACAGAUAUUGUGCCAGGGGUGAGCACCCUGUUUUCCUGGUCCUCACUCUCCUGGGCACUGGUGUCCUACACUCGCUUCAUGGGCUUCAUGAAGCCAGGCCACCUGGCCAUGCCAUGGGCCGCCCUCUUCUGCCAGCAGCUCUGGAGGAUGGGCAUGUUGGGAACCCGCGUGCUGAGUCUGGUUCUGUUCUACAAAGCCUACCACUUUUGGGUUUUUGUGGUUGCAGGUGCCCACUGGCUGGUGAUGACAUUCUGGCUUGUCGCCCAGCAGAGUGACAUCAUCGACAGCACCUGCCACUGGAGGCUGUUCAACCUGCUCGUGGGGGCCGUGUACAUCCUCUGCUACCUCAGCUUCUGGGACAGCCCUUCUAGAAAUAGGAUGGUCACGUUCUACAUGGUCAUGCUGUUGGAGAACAUCAUCCUGUUGCUGUUGGCCACCGACUUUCUCCAGGGGGCAUCGUGGACCAGCCUGCAGACCAUAGCUGGGGUCCUGUCUGGAUUUCUGAUUGGCAGUGUCUCACUGGUAAUUUAUUACAGCCUGCUGCAUCCAAAAUCCACAGACAUCUGGCAGGGCUGCCUAAGGAAGUCCUGUGGCAUUGCAGGAGGUGAUAAAACAGAGAGAAGAGAUUCUCCCCGGGCCACAGAUCUAGCUGGGAAGAGAACCGAGAGCUCAGGCUCAUGCCAAGGGGCAAGUUAUGAACCAACCAUUUUAGGGAAGCCCCCUACCCCUGAGCAGGUCCCCCCAGAGGCUGGGCUGGGGACCCAGGUUGCUGUGGAGGACUCUUUCCUCAGUCAUCACCACUGGCUGUGGGUGAAACUUGCCCUAAAAACAGGAAAUGUGUCUAAGAUCAAUGCCGCCUUUGGAGAUAACAGUCCUGCCUAUUGUCCACCUGCAUGGGGGUUGAGUCAACAGGACUACCUGCAGAGAAAGGCCUUGUCUGCCCAGCAAGAGCUCCCAUCCUCAUCCCGUGACCCCUCAACCUUAGAGAACAGCUCUGCGUUUGAAGGUGUCCCUAAAGCAGAGGCCGACCCAUUGGAAACCUCAAGUUACGUAUCUUUUGCCAGCGAUCAGCAGGAUGAAGCACCUACCCAGAACCCAGCAGCCACGCAGGGGGAGGGCACCCCAAAGGAAGGAGCUGACGCUGUUUCUGGGACACAGGGGAAGGGGACAGGUGGGCAGCAGAGAGGAGGGGAAGGACAGCAGAGUUCCACGUUGUACUUCAGCGCCACUGCAGAAGUGGCCACAUCCUCACAACAAGAAGGCAGCCCAGCUACUCUGCAAACGGCCCACUCUGGAAGGAGGCUGGGAAAGAGCAGCCCUGCCCAGCCUGCAUCGCCCCACCCAGUGGGCUUGGCGCCCUUCCCCGACACCAUGGCCGACAUUAGCCCCAUCCUAGGCACAGGCCCAUGUAGAGGCUUCUGCCCCAGUGCAGGCUUCCCUGGAAGAACCCUCAGUAUCUCAGAGCUAGAGGAGCCGCUGGAGCCCAAAAGGGAGCUAAGUCACCAUGCAGCUGUUGGUGUGUGGGUGUCAUUGCCACAGCUGAGGACUGCCCAUGAGCCCUGCCUCACGUCCACCCCUAAGUCUGAGUCUAUCCAAACGGACUGCAGCUGCAGGGAACAGAUGAAGCAAGAGCCGAGUUUUUUCAUCUGACCACAGUCAUGGUGGGAUAAGACAACAGGCUGACAAACCAAGCUGGCCAUUUGGUACCGUGAGAAAGGAAAUCCCACUUCUGACACCUGUGUCCUUGGGCACAUCACUGUCACCUCUGAAUCUCCAUCUGCAUCCCUGAAAAAUGAAGAAACAGGGCUGGAUGAUUUUGCAGGUCCAAUGCAAACAUCACAGACCCCACCCAUGCAUAGGAGAGACUCUAACAUACUUUAGAGGAGGAGAAAGAGAUUCCAGUCAAAAUUGUCUGCUACCUUUUAUGAGCUGUAGGUUCCCUUAUUUUAUCUUUUUGCUGUGGCUUCUAGGAAACACAAAGGUAAAACCCAGAUUCCUAUUUUAUUUGAGGUUCUUGUUACAAUUAGCUUUGCCUCACAUUUAGCGGUUAUGAAUCUCAUUUUAAUAUAUUCUAACUGUAUUAUGUUAUGAAAUCUCUUGGUAAGAUAAUUUGCAUGCUUUCUGGGAGUAGGUAAGGCCUGUGUGCUUGUAAUAACUAACAUAACUGAAAGUGCAAAUGUCAUUCUAAGAUUCCCAUAUCUUUUGGUUAGGGGACAAUAUUAGAGCUUUUAAAAAGGAAGGGUAGACUCACUUAGCUCAGCCUCACCCAUGCUAAGGGCACAUGCACACAUUUUCUGCAAUUCACUCUCAGACCAUCAGCAUCCUCCUGGCCAGCUGCAUAAAUGUAUUUUUCUGUGAAAUGUGCUGCUCCCCUUUGUGCAGGCUGGCCAGCCAAGAGUUCCCUUCCAGCUCCCACUGCUGCUUUCCACCCCAUCUCCUUUAUGUCCAAGCUUUGUUCCCACUUCCAUUCAAUGUGAGACACUAUCCAUGAUUUAAGCCCAUCCAAAAAGAAGGGAGGAAACGUCCAUUCCUCUCGCACUCUCCUUCUCUCUGACUCCUCCACUCUAAAGUGUUCUUUGUGGCUAGGUAUUUCCAUAAUUUCUUUAAGCCUUCCUUUGUAGCUGAUUAAGGAAGUCUAGUCAUAAACUAUCAAAGAGAAAGGCACACAGAGAGCUGGAUGCUAUUUAGGGAUGGGUAUUUUUGUUUUGUUUUGUUUCAUUUCAUUUGUUUAUUUGUUGAGACAGGGCCUCUCUGUCACCCAGGCUGGAGUGCAGUGGCAUGAUCAUGGCUCACUGCAGCCUCAACCUCCAGGGCUUAAGCAAUCCUCUCACCUCAGCCUCUCGAGUAGCUGGGACUACUGGCAGGUGGGCACCAUGCCUGGCUACUUUUUUGUAUUUUUUGUAGAGACAGGUUCUUGCCAGGUGGCUCAGGCUGGUCUCCAACUCCUGAGCUCAAGCGAUCUGCCCAUCUCGGCCUCCCAAAGUGCUGGGAUUACAGGCGUGAGCCACCGUGCCCAGCCAGAAUGGGUAGUUUUUAUUCUCUCCAAACACUUUUGGAUUAGGGUACAAUAUUAGAGCUCUAAAAAGGAAUAGUAGAAUAACUUAGCUCAGCCUGACACAUACUAAGGGCACCUGCAGACACUUUCUGCAAUAAGCUCUCAGACCAUCAGCAUCCUCCUGGCCAGCCACAUAAGCCAAUCGGGGAUGCAGACAAGUGGCUACAAACUUUCCAUACAACAGGUGAAGAUAACGAGACUUUGGGUCGGAUGCAGGGGCUCACACCGGUAAUCCCAGCACUUUGAGAGGCUGAGGCGGGAAGAUCACUUGAGGCCAGAAGUUCGAGACCAGCCUGGGCAAUGUAGUGAGACCCCAUCACUACUAAAAAUACAUAAAUUAUCCUGGUGUGGUGGCACACACCUGUAGUCCCAGCUGCUCGAGAGGCUGAGGCACGAGAAUCAGUUGAACUGGGAGGCAGAGGUUGCAGUGAGCUGAGAUCGUACCAUGGCACUCCAGCCUGGGCGACAGAGCAAGACUCUAUCUAAAAAAAAAGCUUGUUAAUAGAACAAAAUCAUUCAUAGUUCCAUUCACUGUGCUAUCCCAGCAUCUCAGUCCUUCCUCCAUGCAGUCUCUCGCCCAGCCAGGUGAGAGCAUGAGCACUUCCCUGAGUCCUCACCAGCCCUCCCCAUUUGUCCUCCAAGACUCCACUCAAACAUCUCCUCUUGGUGCCUUCCUGGGCCCUCCCCAGCUCCAGCUCUCCCAGACCUACCCUCUGUCCCCAGGUUGUAUUCCACUGCCCUUUGCCCUCUGGUGACCUCUUCCUAAACUUGAAGCCCUGCCUCCCUGAAGGCUAAUUAAGGGUUGCAGUCCUCCUUCUGGGCUAACUCCAAGGUCCAGCAGAGUGUCCAGCAAAAGUAGGCGUUAGAGCAUUCAACAGCAUGAAUUCACUAACGAGCGGGGCUGUGGGCAUGAAUUUCAGCUUGAGUGCAUAUCCUGGAUCAACGGCAUUUGUGUUAUGGGGUAAAAGUAAGGGUGGGAUAUGGGGAAUUUGCUCAUUCUUUUCAAACUUUCUAGCCCUUGAAUAGCCUGGAAAGCUAGAAAUACUCUUCAUUCAUUCAUUCAUUUAAGGAAUAUUAGUUGAGUAUGACAGGCACUGAGUAUGCAGAAAUCAAGGCAUGUACUUGCUGUUCGAGGCCCUGUGGACCAACAUCGGCUUCUCAGAUGGCUUCCUCACUUCAUGCCUCCAGAAAGCAUAUUGCCCGGUGAUGAAAAGGAUCAGAAAAUAUACACUAUAUUUAUUAGAGAAGACUAAUAAAUGGACACUUAAUUCAAAAA